AGACACGCGUGGCGCGGGCCGCCGUUUCCGCAAACAGAAUCGCGUUUGGCUGUGCUGGAUGUGUGAACCUAUUGGGUACUGUACAACUUCAAGCCUCGAAAUCAGAUAGGCACCACCAACCUCAUUUCCUGUUUCACCUUGAUUUUCUGUGAUACCAAAAUCUCAGCUUCACAAAGUCAUUGAAAGUGUUGGUUCAUGAAGUUUUACCAUCAAUUCAAGUAAUCAUAAAUGGCAAAUUCUGCAAAAGCAGAAGAAUAUGAAAAGAUGUCUCUUGAACAGGCAAAAGCGUCAGUGAAUUCUGAAACAGAGUCUUCAUUCAAUAUUAAUGAAAACACAACAGCUUCUGGGACUGGGCUUUCUGAAAAGACUUCUGUCUGUAGGCAAGUAGACAUAGCAAGAAAGAGAAAAGAGUUUGAAGAUGAUCUUGUAAAGGAAAGUUCUAGUUGUGGGAAAGACACUCCAUCCAAGAAGAGAAAACUUGAUCCUGAAAUUGUCCCAGAGGAAAAAGAUUGUGGUGAUGCUGAAGGCAAUUCAAAGAAAAGAAAAAGAGAAACUGAGGAUGUUCCAAAAGAUAAAUCUUCUACUGGAGAUGGCACUCAAAAUAAGAGAAAAAUAGCACUUGAGGAUGUUCCUGAAAAGCAGAAAAAUCUGGAAGAAGGACACAGCUCAACAGUGGCUGCCCAUUACAAUGAACUUCAGGAAGUUGGUUUGGAGAAGCGUAGUCAAAGUCGUAUUUUUUACCUAAGAAACUUUAAUAAUUGGAUGAAAAGUGUUCUCAUUGGAGAAUUUUUGGAAAAGGUACGACAGAAGAAAAAACGUGAUAUCACUGUUUUGGACCUGGGAUGUGGUAAAGGUGGAGAUUUGCUGAAAUGGAAAAAAGGAAGAAUUAACAAGCUAGUUUGUACUGAUAUUGCCGAUGUUUCUGUCAAACAGUGUCAGCAGCGGUAUGAGGACAUGAAAAAUCGUCGUGAUAGUGAAUAUAUUUUCAGUGCAGAAUUUAUAACUGCUGACAGCUCAAAGGAACUUCUGAUUGACAAAUUUCGUGACCCACAAAUGUGUUUUGACAUCUGCAGUUGUCAGUUUGUCUGUCAUUACUCAUUUGAGUCUUAUGAGCAGGCUGACAUGAUGCUGAGAAAUGCGUGUGAGAGACUUAGCCCUGGGGGCUAUUUUAUUGGUACUACUCCCAAUAGCUUUGAAUUGAUAAGACGCCUUGAAGCUUCAGAAACAGAAUCAUUUGGAAAUGAAAUAUAUACUGUGAAAUUUCAGAAGAAAGGAGAUUAUCCUUUAUUUGGCUGCAAAUAUGACUUCAACUUGGAAGGUGUUGUGGAUGUUCCUGAAUUCUUGGUCUAUUUUCCAUUGCUAAAUGAAAUGGCAAAGAAGUACAAUAUGAAACUAGUCUACAAAAAAACAUUUCUGGAAUUCUACGAAGAAAAGAUUAAGAACAAUGAAAAUAAAAUGCUCUUAAAACGAAUGCAGGCCUUGGAGCCAUAUCCUGCAAAUGAGAGUUCUAAACUUGUCUCUGAGAAGGUGGAUGACUAUGAACAUGCAGCAAAGUACAUGAAGAACAGUCAAGUAAGGUUACCUUUGGGAACCUUAAGUAAAUCAGAAUGGGAAGCUACAAGGUCUUUCCUCCAUGGCGGAAAUACUCUUGAUGGAUGGUGGUUGCCGAAGAUUGGUGUGGCUGUGGCAGUUAAGACAAUGAAGUUUGCCUCAUUGAUUGACCAUUCUUUCACAGAAGAUUUCUCUGUAGCAUGCAGUGCUGUUUGAUAGCGUUUUACCCACUGUAGAACUUAUUUCUAAAUUGGAGUCACUCCUCUGAAACCCUACUGGUCUUUAUCAACUAAGUUUUUGUAAUAUUAAUAUUCGAAAUCCUUGUCAUUUCAACAAUGUUCCCAAUGUGUUUACCAGAAGUAGAUUCUAUCUCAAGCUCAUCCAUAAGAAGCAGCUCUUCAUUUGUUCAAGUUUGAUCAUGAGAUUGCAGCAAUUCAGUCACAUCUGCAGGCUCCACUUCUAAUUCUGGUUCUCUUGUUGUUGCCAUCCCGUCUGCAGCUACUUCCUCCACUGAUGUGUUGAACCCCUUGAAGUCAUGCAUGAGGGUUGGAAUCCAGUUCUUCUAAACUUGCGUUCAUGUUGAUAUUUUGACCUCAUCCCAUGAAGCAUGAACAUUCUUAAUGAUAUCUAGAAUGGGGAAUCAUUUCCAUCAGGUUUUUUAUUUACUUCAUCCAGAUCCAUCAGAGGAAUCACUAUCUAUGGCAGCUAUAGCCUUACAAAAUGUAUUUCUUAAAUAAUAAGACUUAAAAAUGAAAAGUACCCCUUGAUCAAUGGGCUGCAGAAUGGAUGUUGUAUUAGCAGCCAUGAAAAUAACAUUGAUCUCCUUGUACAUCUUCAUCAGACCUCCUGGGUGACCAGGUAUAUUGCCAAUGAGCGGUAAUAUUUUGAAAAGAAUUUUAUUUUUCUGAGCAGUAGGUCUCAACAGUGGGCCUAAAAUACUCAGUAAACCGUGAUGUGAACAGAUAUGCUGUCAUCCAGGCUUUGUUCCAUUUAUAGAGCAUGAGCAGAGCAGAUUUUACAUAAUUCUUAAGGGCCUCGGGAUUUUUGGAAGGAUAAAUGAGCAUUGGCUUCACCUUAAAGUCACUAGCAGCAUUAGUCCCUAACAGGAGAGUCGCCCUGUCUUUUGAAGCUUUGAAACUAGGUAUUGACUUCUCUCUAGCUAUGAAAGUCCUAGAUGGCAUCUUCUAAUAGAAGACUGUCUCGUCUUCAUUGAAGAUCUUAUUUAGUGUAGCCACCUUCAUCAAUGAUCUUAGCUAGAUCUUCUGCAUAACUUGAUGCAGCUUCUACAUCAGCACUUGCUGCAUCAUCUUGCACUUUUACAUUAUGAAGGUGGCUGCUUUCCUUAAACGUCCUGAACCAACUUCUAGUUUCAGACUUUUCUUGUGCAGUUUCCUCACCUCUCUCAUCCUUCAUAGAAUUGAAGAGAGAGAGUUAGGGCCUCUGAAUUAGGCUUUGGAUAAAGGGAAUGUUGUGGCUGGUUGAUCUUUGCAGACCACUCAGACUUUUUCUGAAAAUCAGCAGUAAGGCUGUUUGCUUUCUUAUUCCAGUGUGUUCAUUGGAGUAGACUUUUAUUUUAAGAACUUUUCCUUUGCAUUCAUAACGGCUGAUUUCAAGCCUAGCUUUUUGCCUAUUUUAGCUUUUUACAUGCCUUGUUCACUAAGCUUAGUCAUUUCUAGCUUCUGAUUUAAAGUGAGAGAUGUGCAAGUCUUCCUUUCACUUGAACAUGUGGAGACCAUUGUAGGAUUAUUAACUGGCCUUAUUUCAAUAUUGUUGUAUCUCCAGGAACAGAGAGGCCAAGGAGAGGGAGGGAGAGAGAUGAGGGAACAGCUGAUUAGUGGAGCAGUCAGAGCACACAUGACAUUUAUGAGUUCUCCAUCUUAUAAAGGCACCUCGAUAAAGUUUGUGGCACCUCAAAACAAUUACAGUAAUAACAGCAAAGAUCACUGAUUACAGAUCAUCAUGACAAAUAAUAAUGGAAAAGUUUGAAAUAAUGCAAGAAUUACCGUAAUGUGACAUAAAAACCCGAAGCGAGCAUGUGCUGUUGGAAAAAUGGUGCCAGUAGACUUGCUUGAUAUGGUAUUGCCACAUACCUACAAUUUGUAAAAAACACCAAUUUGUAAAGCUAAAUAAAGCUAGGUAUGCCUUUAAUAGGUUUCAACUUGAUUCAGAACAAGGAAUCCUAAAUUCAUUUAGCUGUCUUUGAGUCAAAGCAGGAAACCUUAUUUCAGGGAGAGAGCUCUUGGGGCUAAUACAUGUAGAAAUAGAAAUAAUAUCUCUGAAGUAUUGAUUGUCGUAGAGCUUUUGGCUUACUUUCUUCACAAGGCCCUACAACACAAUAAUUGGAUAAUUGGGUGAAUUGUUAACAUGUCAUGUUAUGUAUGUUCCUUUAAUUCUAGUUUUCUAAAAUAUCUUUAAUAUUUUUAAUUCUAGUUUUCUUUGUUAUACUUAUUUAAAAUUUAAUUUUAUUAUAAUUUUAAUUUGUUAUACUUCUAAUUUAGUUAUACUUUUAUUUUUCUUACCUUAAACUGAUUUUUAGAGCUGUUGAACUGGUUUUCCCAUGGGCUGCAAUAUCACUGAGUAUUAUAGUAAGUAGAUAAUUGUUUUAAAGUAAGCAAGUACCAUCCCAUGUCUGCCUAAAAAUGAUUCAAAUAAUAGAGGAACUCUUAGAAUUAAUGGGGAUUUUCCUCUUCAGAAGCUGCUUGAGAGCCUAAGAAUUUUCACCAAAUUAUGAACAAGACAGAUUGUUUUAUUUAUUGUAAUCAUAUGAGAAACUGAACUCUUAUUUAUUUCUUCUUUAGGUAUUUACUUGGUGUUUGCCUUUGAGAAACAGCAGUGAGCACAUAGGCAGUAGUCCCAGAGGGGCCGUGUUCUGUCCUGCACAAAUUUGAACAACUCAUCUCGAUAUAUUUGAUAUUUCUCUGUCUGUUGAUUUUAAUUCUAAAUGUGCAGGAUGCUGCCAGAAACUCCAAUGUAGAAAUUCAACAUUUGCUGUCUGUGACAGAUGAACUUUUGCAUGUGUAUAUAAGAAUGAGUUGGGACCUCUGUCUUUAAAAAUCUAUUUUUAGGUAAUGUUCUAAGAAUUCCAUUUGCCUCUAUGAUCUUAGCUCAUAAAAAUAUAAUAUGACUUGAUAAAGCAACUAAACUCUUUCCACAGUGUUCAGAUUUGUCCUGUGUGUGUUUACAGUAUUCAAUUUAUUGCAGUUAUAGAAUUGGUCAGAGAGCAUUUUCAUAGUGUGCUCAUUUCUAUGGUUUUGUUAUAUAGCAUUUUUCAACAUUUAAUGGUCUGUACAGUUGAAUGUAAGUGUUCAAUAUGUAUUGCUGAAGUUAUAAGUUUAAAACUCAAUUUCAGAUGCUCAUAAAAGUUACUUAGCUAAAAUUUUAGCAAUUUAUUGCAUUUUGAAAUAAUCAUUAACAUGCUGCAAUUCAGGAGCUGGUUAGAACAUUUUAAGUGGCAGCAUAGAAUUUUGGAAUUUUGGGGCUUUCUUUUCAGAAAUUGCUACCAUAGUAAUUAAUGUUUCCAGUUAUCAAGAUUGUGAUUAGACACAUUUACCUUUCUUCAUUGAACAAAUGGUGCCAUAGUUAUUUUUCUCAAAAUUUAGUGAAAAUCCCUCCCAUGUAGACAUGUUGCACAUUUUUUCCAAAUUUAUACAUGGAACUGCAGUAGGAAUAUUCUCACCAUCUGAUGCCAUGUACCCACUUCAGAAAUAAGCAAUACUUGUUCCUCUGUUACAACCUCAGCACUUUGCACCGUAGGAGCCAUUGUUAAAGUUGUCACUUGUGUAACUGACUGCUUUUCCAAAACUGGUACUUAUGUGAACUGUUGUCCUUGCUUUACACCACCAUUUGGAAAACUUACCAGUUUUUAGAUGUAGAUGUAGUGAAAAACUUCAAGAAUGAAGCAGAGCAAUUGAGUAUUCUUUUUUAAAUUAUUAAGCCAUGAUUUACAAAAACAUUACUUUCUGUAAUUCACAAUACUUGUUUUAAAAACAUAGUGUCUUCAUUAGUGUGCAUCUAUUAACUGUUCAUGGUGUUAGAGUUGCAAACUUUUUAGCAAGAAAAUAUGGAUUUCCUCAUUUCAGUUCCUUCUGCAGCCUGUGAAUCUCCACAAAGUGUUACCAGUUUACAAAAAUAAGUCUUUUUGCCUUAAGUCAUUUUGGAAAUAAGUAAUACUGCAUCUGACUCUGGUGGCUGUAUUAGCUAGGAAAGGUUUGUAAAUGGUGUCAGUGAGGUGGGGAAAGGAAGUCUUCCUGUCACAUAUGCAGGUUCGUUUUCAUUCUAGGGCAGUGCCAGGAAGUAUAUUGAUAGCUUUGUAGGUACAGGAAAAACAUCAUCAUUAUUUCCUCUGUUCACAUUUACUGGUCUUAAUUAACAGGUAAUAAUAAUACAUGUACUUUUAGCCUGAAACCUCUUCCACGCCAUGGGUAACUUGGGGGAGAGAAGAAUCCUCCAAACGAUGGAGUAGCCAGUGGUAAUACAAAGCAGGGAGAACAGAAAGGUAGAGUUACUAAGGCCUUCAGUGAACAGAAAGGAGCAGAGAGCAAGAUUAGAUCUGAGAAGAUGCUCUGGGGACUGAGCCCACUGUUGUUGGUGUCAGGGAGGCUUACUGGAGCCACACCUGCAGGCGCUGUGUUCAGGCACCACCUUCCUCCUUGAGCUUUGCCUGUCUCUUGCCUUAUCAGUUCUUCCUCCACCACCCUACACCCCCCUCCCCCCGGCCCCAAGCCCCUGUGUCUCCUUGUUACAAUUAAGUUUCUGGAUAUUGACUUAAGAACUGUUAGGAAGAGGACUAGAAAAGGCUUCCCCUGCCUAUCCUCUCCGAUCACCAAGGUGGAAGGGAGCUAGUAGGACUCUUCCUUGACACACCUUGUCGUCUAAAUGUUCGGUAUUCUAUUCAGGACUUACGGUAACUAUUAUGAGGGAGGCAUGGCUUUCCACCGUCGGGCCAGGAAGAGCACCUGUUGCUGCAAGCUCAGUGAAGUGGGGCACUCCCAGACCUGCCAUGCAGUUUAUCCUCUGAGAAUGGAAUUGGAAAUGAAGACCUAACCAGCUAUUGGUGGGAAUGACGGAACUGGGGAUUGCGAUGAUUGAUCUGGGAACAUGGCUGGAUUGUGAUUUAACCAAGAAUGCUGAUGUUGAAUUCUUUGGGCCUAGAAUAUACUUGAGAAAGCACUAGUGGCUUGUGUUCAGGGAGAGGAGCUGGCAGUUUUUAACCACUUCUGUGGGAGCCGUGUUCUAACCUGUGGAAAGUAUUGCAAUUCUGUGAGAGUGACUCUGCAGAGUCACUGCACCAUCAGGCUUGGCCCUGCUGUGCCUUCAGUACCCAGCCAGGUUCUCUGGGUCCAGGGUGACUCUCCAAAGAAAUUGGCCUUCAGCUGGAGAAAACAUUGGGUGGAGACUCUCACUUAUGUUAAUGCAAUCUUGAAAUGACUGAAAGGUAGAUUGCCAGCACAGUGAGUUUCCCAGCCUGCUCCCCCAUCCACACUUGGAAAUUGAGGGAGCAUGACCGCUCUCUGACUUCACAUGUUAAUAGAGGAUCAGAGCAGAGUUGGGAGUAUAUUGGUCAGGAUCAUAGAAAAGAAGACAAAGCUUGCUCAGCCAUGAGAUGGCCAGGUAUCCAGUUUUGUUAACUCUCUUUGGGAAUUUCUUUUUCAGCCUGUUUUUUAGCUUAGUGCCAUUAUGUCAUUUUGAUUUGUAUUCAAGUACUCUUCAAGUAUCUUUGUAAUGAAGGUUUGGCUACUUGUAUAGGUCUGCCUGCAGGGUGAAAAUGCCAGUGUGAAUAUUCUAGCUACCAAACAUUGUUUUUUGUUGAAAAACUGACUUUCUGUUGUCUACCUCAGGCCUUGUGCAUUUGGGUUAUCUCAAGCCAGUCACCACAGAGGGUCUCUAGGGUCUGCAAAAUAGAGGCCAAAUCCAGGGACCAGGCCCUAAUAAUAGAAGUUGUACCAAAAUGCCUGUGGUACUUGAUGGCCUGUUGGUCAAAUAGGAAGUACAAGUGUGUGAUGUUAGAACCUCCCUAGUUGCUGCUAUAUCAAACACUGCACACUUGACAAGUGUUUUCAUUCCCCGCCCUCUGACAGAACAACAUUCCUAAUUCUUUGAAGGCAACCAGUGCAAAGGCUACUACACUUGUGUAAUGAUAUUUAGCAGAUGCAUACAGGACUGGAUCCCAGGGCACUGUCAGUUCUUCCCUCCCUCUCGUGCUGCUCAGUUUGUCCUCUGCUCCCAUGUAGGCCUAAAGUCACCCCACUCCUUAGUGCCUGCACCUCACCACGAUAUUGAGGAAGCACAGGACAUCCAAGGGUACUCUCCAGUUUGGCUGUGGAGACUUGAGCAAGCCCUAAAGUCCCCUGCUCCCUGGACUUCUCCUGGGUUGUGCUUUUUUGGGGGCAACAUACCUUGGACAAAGCUGAGCUGACAGCUAAUGUUUAUUAGCCUCCUACCUAAGUCAGUCACUUUGCUAAAUUCUUCACCUGUGGUAACUCAUUUUGAUUGUUAUAACAUCUCAGCACCGUUAUUCCCAUUUUAAUGAUGAGGAAACUGAGUCAUAGAGGAUACAGACUUGCCCAAAGGAGAGCCAGGAUUUUCACACCCCCUCCUCAAGCUGGGCCUGCCCUCCAAGUGCUUGUUAUAUACCUCCACGGGUGUCAGCCCAGAUGACUCCUCACCCAUCCACCACCUGCAGCUUGAGAUGUUAACUAUUAGAGCUCCAUUCUUUUGGUUCAAAACGUUGAUACUUACUUAGAUGUUCCCUGAGAGGAGUGUUUAUUUCUGAGUAAGGGGCUUUGUUGAAAGAGGGGGUUAGAGAGAGCAAGACAGCACUUGAGUGCACUGGCAGGAAGCAGAGAUAAGACUUGAAUUUCAGUUUGGUAGACCACCUUCUUUAGCAGCCCAACCUGUAGCAAAUCUAGUUUAGCCUGCAUGGCAGGGAGAGGGAUUCUCUUCCCACCCUCACCAUUUGCAAGUGGCAGGAGCUGAGAAUGCCAGUACGAGAGUGUAGCCAAAGUGAGAGGCUGAGAGCAAAGGAGACAUUUUUUUCAGUUUUGAGUCGAGUAUCCAGACAGAGGCAAAUCAUUUUGUUUAACUUUUUAUUAAAGUGUAACUAUAGAAACACAUCAAUGAUUUUUCACAAGUGGAGCACGUGCAUACAAUCGGCACCCCAGAAGCCCCCCGUCAGAUUCCCUUCCAGUUAACUACCUCUCCAAGGGAAACCACUAUCCUGAGUUCUAAGCGCAUAGAUUAGUUCUGUCUGGUUUGGGGAGAUAUAUAAAUGGAAUUAUGCAUUCUUCGUAUCUGGUUUCUUUUCACCAAUAUUAUGUUUGUGAGAUUUUUGUUGCAUGUAUUUGUACAUGGAUUUUCAUUCUCAUGGUUGUAUAAUAUUUCAUUGUGUGAAUAAACCACAUACUGUUUAUCUGA